GCCUUCCCUCCGCGCCUCGGCCGCGUGGCUUGCGGCUUAUUUUCCCAGCUGGCAAGCGUCGCGCUGCAGACAAGGGAAUGCCUGUGGUGAGUUGUUUAUUUUGUUGAAGUUUGCGGUGGGCCCGGGGGACGUGGGGGGCGAGCGGCAGGCAGCGGCCGGGACUGUUUUGUUUAGGUCUCCAUCCACCUGUGGGGUAUAAAUCUGCCAGCCUCAAGGCGGCGGGGGACCGGAGUGAGAAAGCUCUGACGCUCCCAAAAGCCCCUUUUCGCAACUUACAGAUCUAGGACCACAUUUGAUUCUCCACGCCUGGAACCGGCUAGAUCCUAGUUUACGCUCACCCCGCCCUCCAGCCUCCCAUCAACGCUUCCCGCACCCGCUGUGUGCAGGGCUGGCGCUCCGCAGAGCAAACAGCGCCCACGACCCAGGGACAGCUGGCCACCGAAGUCCCUCCCCGGCGCCCUUCCCCGUUCCUUGAGGAUAGGGGAGCUGAGGUUUUCAUGUGAAGGGCGCCCAUGAAAUUCGUGGGAACUUGUUCUGGCGUCUUCUGGAGUGGAGUUCUUUCAGGGGUUUCGGGUCUGCCCGGGACUACAAAAUGGGAUCCUGGGUUGGCUGGAGUUUCCCAGACUAGGCUGGAGAGAGGUCGGCUGUUGGCUCGCGGGAGAGCCCAGAGGAACCCCUUGGGCGAUGGCAGUCAAGACCGGCGGCUGCGUUUGCCUGGAAGAAAAGCCUAAAUACAUUAGCGAGCUGGUAAAGCUUUUAAGGCCUUCUUGGGAGCGAGUGGCUGGCUAAUGAGAGGUUAAUUUUGUUUCGAAGGGAAGGCUGCACUGGUUUCCUGAGAUAAAUGGACAGGAAGCGCAUUACCUCCGCGCGCUGGCAAGCGGCUCCCAAAUGCUUUUUGCACCUGCCGUUUUGAGCGGUGAGAGCAGCGGCGGAGCCCGCAGGGAUUGCGGGGGCCCGUUGUCUACGAGCGGGUGAUGAGCCCCCCGCAAGCCCCGGGCUCUCUCCCUCCGCGAGUGCAUUGCUCACGCCAAGCUUUGGGACUCUUCUCUCACACCCAGGUCCUGCGUGUUCCGAAGUUCAGGGGCCCCCUGAUCCCGCUGAGCCCCCUCCAGGAGCGAAAGGGUUAAGAAUGAUGUAAGUACAGGCACUUGAUUUCUCAAGUCGCCCGCUUGGCCCUCUUCCAAGUUGUACUUUCCUUAUUUUCUCUCCUUUCCUUUCCUUACUGUUCUAACGCUUUUUAAUAAACUUUCACUCUUGCUCUGAAAAAAAAAAUGAUGUAAGUACAAACCACGAGCUGCUUGACGCUGAGCUGUUGGACUCCGGGCUAUUUCAGCCGCUGCUUUGGGUACACAGUGGCCGGGGAGCAGCCGGGGAGCCCUUACUCUAGAAAGGAUUGCACAAAUCGCAAGCUUAGGUGAUCUGUUAAGCAGUCAGAGAUUCUCCUGUUAGAUUUCUGGAAAUGGAGACAUAUUAACUGGAGAACAGUUAAAAACAUCACGUAUAGGCUCAGGAAAUGAAACUGCAUCUUGUUUAGAAUCCAUUAGUGUUUCUGGCAUGUGUUUUAAUUCUGUCCACUUGCACGUUCAUGCCGUAGUAUGCUUUGCUGGAUUCUCCGGAUGUACUGUUCAGGUCUCCUCCUUCCUUUCUGAAAACAAAGAGAAAGGGAGAAAGAGUACCAGUGGCAAGAAACAGGGUGGAUGUGUGAAUUACACAAGUCAUCAGCCACUUCAUGAUUUUUUUUCUGAUUAAAACAUAAAACUUUUAUAAGUCACCGAUUUUUUUGUUUGUGUUCUAGCUCCCUCCCCGAUUUUUCUUUGUACAAUAUAAAGUCGUUUGUAACUUGCAGCUCACGGGCUUGAGGAGUGGCUGCGGUAUAAGCGACUAUUCACUACGCUCUUGCUUUCCAAGCCAAUUCCUGAUCUUGUGAACAGUACGAAUUUACCCGCGAGUGUGUCAACUGACCUAUGUCUUGAAAAUAGGAACCACCUUGCGGUUUACUUGUGAAAAUUAGCAUUUUCCUCUAGCGGCUGAACACUUAUGCAGCAAUAAAAAGUGAAUUGUUAGGCUUAUAAAUCUCGAGCUUGUCAAAUUUUACAACAGAGGAGCAAUAAAGCACCUUAUAGAGAUGAAGUUUUUCCUCUGAAGAACAGUUCCGUUUAACGACACCAGGAUUUGCAAUGACUCGAGGACGCCCUCUAUUGAUAGGAAAAUCUAGAGCACCCGUGUACUUAUGGAACAGGAUAUAGGGGGAGGGGAGUAAAAAAUCAUAGAAAGUCACGAGUGGAAAGACCCAAACCAAACAGAAAUUAUUGAUCCUUAACUAUUGAGUAUAUGCUUUGAAGUAUGAUCAAUAAAGUGAGAUGCUGCUUUUAUAGGGGUCGAAUUAAAUCUUGGGUUAAGAGAAAAAAAUGUAGUCUUUGUUAGCCAAAUACUUUGAAAAUCAGUAUUAUGUUUGAUUACUUUUUUAAGAUGCUUCUUAGUAUGUCAUGAACUGUAUCUAAUUAUAUGAAGUAAUUGCAAGAUAGUAAAUUUUUGCUCUAAUAAUACUUAGUCCGCAGCAUUAUCUAAAAAUGUCAUAUAACUUCCUCCCCAAAAGUCAUUUCUCCAGGCAACUGUGAAGCUAUUAUUAAGCGUAUUAUGGAUAUACACAGGCUUGGAUUAUAUUGUGGAUAGUGAAAGGUGUGUUUACCCCUUAAGUCAUCAUAGUAUGUAACAAGUAAGUAAUGAAAAGUUACAGUAAAAACAGAUAGGCAUCCUUCAUUAGGGACCUAGUGGUUUGGGCAAUUCAAAAUGUGUCUAAUAAGUGAGCUGGUGAGACUGAAGGUUUGCCCCUCAAUUAUCCUAGUCCAUUGAUUAGCUCAUUUAAACAUGUGUGGAAUAUCAGCAUGUCCGUGGUUGAUAAGAAAUUCCUAAUUAGAGAUUCUGAGUAACAUAGCGGGUACAGUUGCCAACUACGAUUUGGAUGUUAGUGGAUUUUAAAUGGCAACCCUGUGCUGUUUGGGGAAAGGCAAAGGCGAGGGCGGUAUCAAGUGUCUCUCAGCCUUGAGGUCAUUCUUGAGAUUAGAUACCACUUCACACCUACCGAUAACAAAUUGGAAUCUAUCAUCAGUCUCAUAACUGCUUUUCUGUCUCCACUUGGCAGCCUCUUUCUUUGUAGACAAUUGUCUUUUUCCUCACUUUCGGACCCAUCCGAUCAUAAAAGGAGAAAGUGAGCUGCCAUUGAAUUAAUCCGUAGAAAUUUGUGGAAAAUUUAAAUAAUCUGUAGAAAUUUGUGAAAAAGCCACUGAGCAACAACAAAUCGUGGCAUAAUUACACUGCAUAAAAACCCACCACUCUCAUUAAUUACACUGUAACCGAACGUUGAAGUUUGCCCACUCUUAGACCUCUCCUUGCCGCUUUCAGGAAGGGAAAUGUCAAACUAGAACACCUGAGCCUCGCACAGCUGCCAGCGAAUUCCGGCGGCAGUUCGCGGGUACCUUCCCAGCCCAUCCUAUCUGCUCCGGACCGCGGGUGACAUUCAGAUUUCCAACACCGCCCCGAGCUUGCUUUACCAGACACCCUCAAACGACUCGGAACGCGGUUCCGCAGAUGUGAUUGGCUGAAAGGGGACCUGCCGCGCGGCGCUCUGUAAAAGCGCCUGCUUCCUCCAAGGAGGUGGAGCUGAAGCUGGCAGGGCCAGGGCAGGGAGGGGUAAUUAAAUUAAAAAAAAAACUUGGAGGGAAGAUGAAUCGGAUCACAUUAAUUCAAGGAGAGGUCAAAGGCCGGUACCUUUGUAACGCCGGCGAGAGUAAGACUUGCGGUCGCCCAUUUCUGUUGGGCGCGAGGAAACAGUAAAUCGCGGAAGGGGGUAGAGGGGGAAGGAAAGGGAGCGCGAGGCAGCAUGCGGCGCAGGAGAGAGGACUUGGAGUCGAUGGACAGGGAACUCGAAUUACACUGAGCGGGCGGGGGAGAGGGCCCUCUGGGUCCUGCGAUUGGCAGGCUGAGUCGGGCUGACAAGGAAGAAGAGGAAGCGAAGCGCGCCCCCCGGCCCAUGCCGCAGCCACGGGCCCAGACCCGCCACGGCGCCCGCGCCGCCGCCCUCGCCGGAGCCCACGAGACCUGCAUGGACGGGCAUGGGCUUGAGAGCAGCACCUUCCAGCGCCGCCGCUGCCGCCGCCGAGGUUGAGCAGCGCCGCAGCCCCGGGCUCUGCCCCCCGCCGCUGGAGCUGCUGCUGCUGCUGCUGUUCAGCCUCGGGCUGCUCCACGCAGGUGACUGCCAACAGCCAGCCCAAUGUCGAAUCCAGAAAUGCACCACGGACUUCGUGUCCCUGACUUCUCACCUGAACUCUGCCGUUGACGGCUUUGACUCUGAGUUUUGCAAGGCCUUGCGUGCCUAUGCUGGCUGCACCCAGCGAACUUCAAAAGCCUGCCGUGGCAACCUGGUAUACCAUUCUGCCGUGUUGGGUAUCAGUGACCUCAUGAGCCAGAGGAAUUGUUCCAAGGAUGGACCCACAUCCUCUACCAACCCCGAAGUGACCCAUGAUCCUUGCAACUAUCACAGCCACGCUGGAGCCAGGGAACACAGGAGAGGGGACCAGAACCCUCCCAGUUACCUUUUUUGUGGCUUGUUUGGAGAUCCUCACCUCAGAACUUUCAAGGAUAACUUCCAAACAUGCAAAGUAGAAGGGGCCUGGCCACUCAUAGAUAAUAAUUAUCUUUCAGUUCAAGUGACAAACGUACCUGUGGUCCCUGGAUCCAGUGCUACUGCUACAAAUAAGAUCACUAUUAUCUUCAAAGCCCACCAUGAGUGUACAGAUCAGAAAGUCUACCAAGCUGUGACAGAUGACCUGCCGGCCGCCUUUGUGGAUGGCACCACCAGUGGUGGGGACAGCGAUGCCAAGAGCCUGCGUAUCGUGGAAAGGGAGAGUGGCCACUAUGUGGAGAUGCACGCCCGCUAUAUAGGGACCACAGUGUUUGUGCGGCAGGUGGGUCGCUACCUGACCCUUGCCAUCCGUAUGCCUGAAGACCUGGCCAUGUCCUACGAGGAGAGCCAGGACCUGCAGCUGUGCGUGAACGGCUGCCCCCUGAGUGAACGCAUCGAUGACGGGCAGGGCCAGGUGUCUGCCAUCCUGGGACACAGCCUGCCUCGCACCUCCUUGGUGCAGGCCUGGCCUGGCUACACACUGGAGACUGCCAACACUCAAUGCCAUGAGAAGAUGCCAGUGAAGGACAUCUAUUUCCAGUCCUGUGUCUUCGACCUGCUCACCACUGGUGAUGCCAACUUUACUGCCGCAGCCCACAGUGCCUUGGAGGAUGUGGAGGCCCUGCACCCAAGGAAGGAACGCUGGCACAUUUUCCCCAGCAGUGGCAAUGGGACUCCCCGUGGAGGCAGUGAUUUGUCUGUCAGUCUAGGACUCACCUGCUUGAUCCUUAUCGUGUUUUUGUAGGGGUUGUCUUUUGUUUUGGUUUUUUAUUUUUUGUCUAUAACAAAAUUUUAAAAUAUAUAUUGUCAUAAUAUAUUGAGUAAAAGAGUAUAUAUGUAUAUACCAUGUAUAUGACAGGAUGUUUGUCCUGGGACACCCACCAGAUUGUACAUACUGUGUUUGGCUGUUUUCACAUAUGUUGGAUGUAGUGUUCUUUGAUUGUAUCAAUUUUGUUUUGCAGUUCUGUGAAAUGUUUUAUAAUGUCCCUGCCCAGGGACCUGUUAGAAAGCACUUUAUUUUUUAUAUAUUAAAUAUUUAUGUGUGUGCUUGGUUGAUAUGUAUAGUACAUAUACACAGACAUCCAUAUGCAGCGUUUCCUUUGAAGGUGACCAGUUGUUUGUAGCUAUUCUUGGCUGUACCUUCCUGCCCUUUCCCAUUGCUACUGAUUUGCCACGGUGUGCAGCUUUUACUCGCCACCUUCCGGUGGAGCUGCCUCGUUCCUUUGAACUAUGCCCUCACCCUUCUGCCCUCACUUGAUUUGAAAGGGUCGUUAACUCUCCCUUACAGGUGCUUUGACUCUUAAACGCUGAUCUUAAGAAGCUCUCUUCAUCUAAGAGCUGUUACUUUUUCAGAAGGGGGGGUAUUAUUGGUAUUCUGAUUACUCUCAAUUCUAAUUGUUAUAUAUUUGAGCCCAUACAGUGUAUUAGGUUGAACCAUAGAAACUGCUAUUCUCGUAGGUCAAAAGGGUCUAGUGAUGGAAGUUUUGUAGAUAAGUACCAGGCAUCUCAGUAACUCCUAGACUUUUUCUCAUCCCAUGCCCCGUUUUAAAUUGUCAGUUUUCCCUCUGACUCUUCUGUGUUAAAACAUGAAACUAUAAAUUUAGUAAUUAUCAUGCCUUGCUCUUUUUAAUCUAUAUGACUGAUGCAAGCCCCUCUUCUUAACCGUUUCUUGGCUUUGAGCCCAGAAACACAGCUCUCCCUGUCUCCAACUCCAGUAAGCCCUCCUCAGCCUCACCUUACGAAUCCAAAGAACUGGGGUUUGUUAGGUUCUUUCUCUAAUGUAGAGGCCCAGAUCCCAUCACAAAGUUUUUCAUUCUUCCUUGUCCACCAUGAUCUUCAUCACAGUCUUUGAUAUGUCUGCAUGCAAAGUGGAACAGAGUUGGGCGGCAAUGACAGAAGAGCUUCCUUGGCCUGACUCGGUGUGCGGCCACUUCGGCACUGCUUAAUCCAGAUAUUCUUGUUAACUAAGCAUUGUGCUUCCCAGGUGGUCUGAAGUCAGGUACUCUCUCUCUCAACACCUGUAGUUGAAUAUGAUUUGGUCAGUUGCUCGUUGUAACUUGGAGAAAUUCCUAUAAAGUAAGAUCUCCUUGCCUCUUCCAUCCAUUGUUGGCACCCCCUUGCAAAAGGAAAAGAACAGCAAAAGUCAGGAGCAGUAAUCUGAGAAAGUUAACUCCAGGAUAGGUAGGUUUCUAUUGUUAUAGCUAGAUGUAAAUCUUUAGUUCCAAGAAGUGAUAGAGUUUCUGCUUUAAUAAUUUGUUGAUAAGUUUACAUAAACAGAAAUAAAAGAUACUAUCUUUACCGUAGUAGUUCAGGCCAAGAUUAUGCUUAGUUUUAGUUCUCCAGGUAGUUACUUUUGCCAUGUCCUAUUGAUCAGUGACACUGCCAGAGGCCCAUACCGGCAAGAGGAAGAGGACGUCAUUUUGUAAAGUUUAACUUCUUAGCGAACUGAUGUGCCACCCAGUCACAGAGUGGAGUUGUGAAUUCAUGUAGAGGUGGCAAACCUCUACCUUGUGUUGAUGAGAGAAUAAUCUUGGGCAGUCUGGGAAAAUAAGGAAGGCAUCUCCUUCUUACUCAUGGAGAUUCAACUAUAGAGAGUUGAAACCUAAACCCGCCUUCCUUUUAUAGAAGCUGGACUAGAGACGGACUGACCAUCAGCUCUGAACUGUGGCUUUUUUUGUUCACCUAUGAUGCCAUGUACCAAAUUCAGAAGCUAUCGUUAAUAAUUUGUUUUAUAAUUGAGUAGUACAAGCGAGGAAAAAAUACGGAGGAUAACCACUAUUUUUGUGCAAAUAAUAUGAAAGUGAAGUAAAAGCAAUAGAAGAAAUUUCUAUAGGAUCUGGGUUUAGAGUGUGUAUCAUUAAUAAAUAUACCUUUGCUCUUUUCAGGGAAAAUAACAACCACCCUUACUGAUAGUUGGGAAAAGAAGAUUGGGUUAUUUUGCCAUAUCAUUUAGCUGGAAGUGACAUUUAAAAGCACCCUGCAUCACUAGUAAUAGUGUAUUUUGCUAUUCUGCCCUUGUAAUCGGUGUCCCUGUAAAACAAUCCCCACAGAUUACUUUCAGAAAUAGAUGUAUUUCUCUACGUAAGGGCCAGGUUUAUUUUCUCCUUUUUUGAGAUUUCUAGAAAAAAUGCUGCUUGCACAUGUUGGUUCUUGAAACCUUAGCUAGAAGAAUUUCAGGUCAUACCAACAUGUGGAUAGGCUAUAGCUGUUCAGAGGUCUCCUGGGGGAGCUUAAAACGGGGGAAACACUGGUUUUCACAGAUGCUCCACAUGGCUGUCUUUAAAAGACUCAAAACUUUUUUUUGUCCUCUUUGUUAUGCUUGGAAGCUCCCCCCCCCCCAACAGUGUGUCGAGUCUUUGCAAAGAAACCUUUAGAUGUGGUUCAUAGAUAUAUGAAUACGUAUCUGUGUAAAACAGUGAGUGUGCAGUGUGUAAAUACUUUAAAUUAUUAUGCUAGAAAAAUAAAGUUACAUACCUUGCUGUGGAA